CUUCUUUUUCUUCAGCGAGGCGGCCGAGCUGGUUGGUGGCGGCGGUCGUGCGGGUUCGCGCCGGGCCGAGAGCGGGUUGGGGGCUGCGGGAGGCUGCAGGGGCCUGGGCGGCAGAAGAGGCGGCCCUGAGCUGGCUCAUGCGGGCCAGUCUCGGCAGGGUGGCUGGGCAGGGCUCGCGAGGCCACGGCUCGGAGCCCAGACCGGGGCCCAGGAGGCGAGCGCCGUUUUGGAGAGGAGCCUGCCUGCUCUGCCUGCCAGCGUGACCCCACGAGGCCUCGGGCGGGAAGAGGUCCUCGGGGCAGAUCCGAGUUAAUGAGAGAGGGGUAUUGAGCGUGUAGCGUUAACUCUGCCAGUCACUGCGUCAGUCGCUUUGGAAAUACUAAAUUUCUCGAGCUGAGUCUUCAUACCUGGCUCCAUUACUACGUCUGUAAGGAGGAGCUGGUGGUAGUGUCUGCUUUUUAGACUUUUCUUUAGACUAUUUGUAUUUUUUUCAGAUGGAGUCUUGCUCUGUCGCCUAAGCUGGAGUUCAGUGGUGCGGUCUCGGCUCACUGCAAUCUCCACCUCCCGGGCUCGAGCGAUUCUUCUGCCUCAGCCUCCCGAGUAGCUGGGAUUAUAGGCGCCUGCCACCACGCCCAGUUGAUUUUUGUAGUUUUAGUAGAGACGGAGUUUCACCAUGUUAGCCAGGCUCAUCUUGAACUCUUGACCUCAAAUGAUCCGUCUGCCUCGGCCUUCCAAAGUGCUGGGAUUACAGACGCAAACAUGCAGAUCUUUGUGAAGACCCUCACUGGCAAAACCAUCACCCUUGAGGUCGAGCCCAGUGACACCAUUGAGAAUGUCAAAGCCAAAAUUCAAGACAAGGAGGGUAUCCCACCUGACCAGCAGCGUCUGAUAUUUGCCGGCAAACAGCUGGAGGAUGGCCGCACUCUCUCAGACUACAACAUCCAGAAAGAGUCCACCCUGCACCUGGUGUUGCGCCUGCGAGGUGGCAUUAUUGAGCCUUCUCUCCGCCAGCUUGCCCAGAAAUACAACUGCGACAAGAUGAUCUGCCGCAAGUGCUAUGCUCGCCUUCACCCUCGUGCUGUCAACUGCCGCAAGAAGAAGUGUGGUCACACCAACAACCUGCGUCCCAAGAAGAAGGUCAAAUAAGGUGGUUCUUUCCUUGAAGGGCAGCCUCCUGCCCAGGCCCCGUGGCCCUGGAGCCUCAAUAAAGUGUCCCUUUCAUUGACUGGAGCAGCAAUUGGUGUCCUCAUGGCUGAUCUGUCCAGGGAGGUGGCUGAAGAGUGGGCAUCUCCCUUAGGGACUCUACUCAGCACUCCAUUCUGUGCCACCUGUGGGGUCUUCUGUCCUAGAUUCUGUCACAUCGGCAUUGGUCCCUGCCCUAUGCCCCUGACUCUGGAUUUGUCAUCUGUAAAACUGGAGUAAAAACCUCAGUCGUGUAAUUGGUGGGACUGAGGAUCAGUUUUGUCAUUGCUGGGAUCCUGUCAGGCACUUUGAGGUGUCCCUCAGGCCUUGGCCCUGAAGUGUCUAGGUGUGUGGAGAUGGGUAGAAAAUUAGGUACACCCAAUGGUGUAGAACGUUGAUUCUCAAAUUUUUUUAUUUUAUACAAAUGGGGUCUCACUAUGUUGUCCAGGCUGGUCUUGAACUCCUGGGCUCAAGCCAUCCGCCCAUCUCAGCCCCUCAAAGUGUUGGGAUUACAAGCAAGAACUGCCAUGCCUGACCCAGUUCUCAGUUUUUUGUUUGUUUGUUUGUUUGUUUGUUUUGAGACGGAGUCUUGCUCUGUCGCCCAGGCUGGAGUGCAGUGGCGCAGUCUCGGCUUACUACAACCUCUGCCUCCGGGGUUCACAUCCUUCUCCUGCCUCAGCCUCCCGAGUAGCUGGGACUACAGGUGCCCGCCACAACUCCUGGCUAAUUUUUUGUAUUUUUAGUAGAGACGGGGUUUCACUGGGUUAGCCAGGUUGGUCUCGAUCUCCUGACCUUGUGAUCCAUUCGCCUUGGCCUCCCAGAAUGCUGGUAUUACAGGCGUGAGCCAGCACGCCUGGCCCAGUUACUCAGUUUUGAAUCUGAGGCCGUGACAUCACUCAUGGUCUGCAGUCAGUGCUCUGCCCCUGAGCUGUACCCUCUCCUAUGAUAAUCACUCUUAAGAAGGGCAACCCUUGGUGUUUUCCCCUUAAGGUCACCCAGGCUGGAAUGCAGUGGUGUGGUCAUGGCUCCCUGUACCCUGGAACUCAGGCUUGGGUGAUCCUCUCUCCUUUGCCUCCGAAGUAGCCAGGACUACAGGUGUGCACCCACCACCACACUCAGAUAAUUGCUUUGGUGUUUUUAAAGCUUGUAAUGAUCAGUAGGCUGAGGUGGGCAAAUCAUAAGGUCAAGAGUUUUUUAGAUGGGGUGAGCACAGACCAAUUCCUGUUUUAUUUACUGAUUUAAAAUUUUGAGACAGUCUCACUGUCACCCAGGUUGGGGUGCAGUGGUAGGAUCAUAGCUUGCUGCAGCCUUGAUCUCCCAGGAUCUUGCCUCAGCCUCCCGAGUAGCUGGGACUGCAUGCUUGUGCCACCACACUCGGUUAAUAUUUUGUAGAGAUGGGGUCUUGCUAUGUUGCCCAGGCUGGCUUCAAACUCCUGAACUUAAAAGCCUCCUGUUUAGUUUUGGUUUUUUAUCACUUUUUUUUUUUUUUUUUGAGAUGGAGCCUUGCUCCCAUCGUGCAGGCUGGAGUGCGGUGGCGCAGUCUCGGCUCACUGCAGCUUCUGCCUCUCGGGUUCAAGCGAUUCUCCUUUCUCAGCCUCUUGAGUAGCUGGAAUUACCAGUGUGCGCCACCACCACCACGCCUGGCUAGUUUUUCUGUUUUUAGUAGAGACAGGGUUUUGCUAUGUUGGCCAGGCUGGUCUUGAACUACUGACCUCUUGUGAUCUACCUGUCUUGGCCUUCCAAAGUGCUAGGAUUACAAGCGUAAGCCACAGCGCCUGGCCUUGCUACAUUUUUUUUUUUUUUUUUUUUUUUACAGACAUGGUCUCGCUAUGUUGCCCAGAAUGGUUUUGCACUGGGUCCAAGCAGUUCUGCCGCAGCCUCCCAAAGUGCUGGGAUUACAGGGGUGAGGCACCUUGCUGGCCCCUGUUUUGAUUAGGGUGCAGUGCUGGUGAAGCCGGUGCACGAGGCCAGUGAUGCAUCCUAAUGAGGGGUGGAGUUGGCGGGACUUCCUGGGCCAGUUUGGGGACUUUCACAAAAGACCCCCAUGACUCAGGGUUUUGAGUUCUUAACUGAUCGAAUGAAGGAUUCAAAAUUAACCACUCCAAGGGGGGAUUGAAGGAAGAACCACUCUUAAUGGACAAAAAGAAAGAAAGGGGAGGGAGUAACAGGGAUAUGAGCUCUAGCCGCCCAAGCUAGCAAUGGCAACCCUUCUGGGUCCCCUUCCAGCAUGUGGAAGCUUUCCUUUCGCUUCAUUCAAUAAACAGCUGCUGCUCACUCUCCUGGUCCGUGGACUCUUUUUGAACUGUUAACACUCCCCGCAAAGGUCCGCAGCUUCAUUCUUCAAAGUUAGCGAGACCAGGAACC